AAAUGAUAAGAAUGUCAAGACGGUGACAACAGAACAUGAAAUCAAGCGCCAGGCCCUGCUGAGCUCAGGGCUCUGUGUGACCGCACAGGUCACACACCCAUGAGACUGGCCUUGUCUUUCGGGUCCUUCACGCCCCACCCACCCAUCUCCUUUACCACAUGCAGACCUCCACUCUCCACACAACCCUUCCUCCAAGAGGACAGUCAAUGGGAAGUAAGAAGAUUUAAAAGACAAGGGGCAAAGAAAAAUGCAAUGGUGUGUUUCCAUUGUAGAAAACCUGGUCGUGGAAUUGCGGAUUGCCCUGCCGCCCUUGAAAAUCAAGAUAUGGGCACUAGAAGAUGUUACAAGUGUGGGUCCACAGAUCACGAAAUAACCAAGUGUAAGGCUAAAGUAGACCCGCCUCUUGGCGAAUGUCCUUUUGCAGAAUGUUUUGUCUGUGGAGAAAUGGGGCACCUGUCUAGAUCUUGUCCUGAUAAUCCCAAAGGACUCUAUGCUGAUGGUAGUGGUUGCCAACUUCAUGGCUCUGUGGAACAUUUAAAGAAAGAUUGCCCUGAAAGUGAGAAUUCAGAUCGAAUGGCCACAGUUGGUCUGUGGGCAAAGGGAAUAAGUGCAGACUAUGAAGACAUUGUGGAUGCACCAAAACCACAAAAACCCAAAACAAAAAUACCUAAAGGUGUUAAUUUUUGAUAACAACUAGUACUGUCAUUAGUUACCACCUCAUUGUUACUUUCUAAACCAGGCCCACUUCACAAGUUACAGCUGGGCUCCCUUGUAG